CCUAUUCCGUUGUGUCACUGGCUCACACCUUGUAAUUGAUUUCCGUUGUACUUGGGAUAAAAUCAAAAAUCUGUGGGGUAAAAAGCCUUGCCUAUGUUUCCAGAAGCCGCUGGACUUGCUCUCCCUCAUCUCUCUUCUCUCUAGAAUGCCUCCCCUCCCCAGCCCCUGGCCUGAGCACCUGCAGCUCACCCUUUCAGUUUCACUUCAGAUGUCGCCUUCUCACACAGGCCCUUCAGUACCACUGCUCCCUCCUCAAACUGACUUAGAUCCUUUUAGUCUUUGUAUGUAUCAUCACUAUUAUUUUAUUCAAUAUCCCUCCCCCCUCUAGACUGUAAGAUCUAUGAGGAUGGCGCUAAGUCUAUUUUGUUCACCACUGUGCUUGCACCUGCCGGCCUGUGACAUCUGCUACUCACUUGGUAAAUACUAUUUCACAGGAGGAUGUUUAUUUCCUGGGAUAGAAUAACCAGGAAAGUGUUCGUGGGGCUGCUGUGGUUAUCCUGAUUCCAUCACCUAAAGGAAAAAGGCACAUCAAAAUUACCAUUUAAACCAUUUUAAGGCCUACAUUCAGCGUCAGGGUAGGCCUUGAUUAGUAUUUCAUCAUAUCAGUCUCACCUCAUUAAGGUGAUAAUAGUCCCUGCUUACAGUGGUUCAACUUAGGAUUUUUGACUUUAUGAUGGGUUUAUCAGAGUAUUAAAUGCAUUUUGACUUACAGUUUUCGACUUAAACCCAUCCUAAGUGAAGGAGCAUCUGUACUAUCAUAACACCACUCUAAUUUAUUAAAAGCUUUCAGGAAAAAGUAUAGAUACGUUUGAAACAUUGGGUUUUCCGUUGUUUCCUAAAGAUAGCUUUAUCAGGGUUUUUUAGCAGGCAUCAGAAUGGCAAAGAAGAUCUUAACAUUUCUUUGUGUCUUCCCAGUUGUAUUUGUAUUGCUUAUACUGCAAUAACAAAAUACCGGUGGACUACCUGGCUUAAACAACAGAAGUUACUUUUCUCACAGUUCUGGAGGCUAGGAAGCCUGGUGAGGCCAGUUAAUGGUGGUGGGUCUCUUCCAGGCUUGUAGCCUUCUUGCUGUGCAUGCACAGGGAGAGAAAGAAAGAGGGAGGGUGAGCCCUCAGGUGUCUCUUCUCAUGAGGACACUAACCCUGUCAGAUCAGGGUCCCAACCUCGUGACCUCAUUUAACUUUACCUCCGAAAGGCCCUUUUUCCAAAUGCAGUCACAUUGGGGGUUAGGGCUUCCAUGUAGGAAUUUGAGAGGGACACAGUUCAGUCUAUAACAGCAGUGAAUUCUUAUUGAUGUAAGAACUUUUUCUAGUGGUAUUUUAAGGUACAAGAUUUCUUAUAAAAUAGAGAUAGUGUGAGCAAAAGCACUGAUGAGGUUAAUUGGUACAGUGGCCAAAACUUCAUAGCAUAUUAGGAAGUAUUUCUUUUUGUAUGCUUUUCUUUUUUUUUUUUUUUUUUAAUUAUCUUGUGGAAAGACUAAAUUUUCCUUUUUAAUUCUGGCUCUGCUUCUCACUAGCUGUGUGAUCUUGGAUAAAUGCUUAAUUCCUUUGUAAAACUCAGUAUUGGUACCCGCCAUGUAGGGUUGUUAUGAGGAUUAGAUGUGGUGAUAGCCGUAAAGCUCCCAGGAUGGAGUCUGACAAACAAUGAGCCCACAUUAAAGCUCCGUUUGACGCACUUGGCCAUCCUUCCCAGUGUGGGGCAAAGUAAAACCAAUUUCUAGGCUAUUGAAGCAGGUGAAUGCACACAGGCUGGCAAUUUCCCAACUGAAUAUGAUUUCUGAGGAGGUGCAAGUAUCCAGUGUCUGCAUUCUAGCAUGCAUGAUCAUCUGCUAGAGUUGCCCUUUUUCUCGUUUAUUUGAAUCUAAACAGUAGAGCAAGUAGAUUGACUAUCUUGGAGUUUAAACACCGAAAACAUCCAAACAUCAGAACUUUUCUCCACAUACUACUGACAUUGAAACAUGUCACGAAACAUGACAUUCUAAUACCAGAACAAUUGGCUUUUGUGCGUGGCAAGGGAUAAUGUGGCAAUCCUCUAUGCUGUGCAUGGCUGCUUGGUCCAUCAUCGUCUGGAUCAUCUCACACAGUUGCUAUGAUAUUAGGAUAACACACAAGUUAUGGCAGUUCUUAGUUUAUGUUUUGCUAGGCACAUUGCACAUGUGUGUGUAUAUAUAUACAUAGGUAUAUGUACAAAUGUGUAUAUGUAAAUAUAUUUGAGUGUGUGUUUGUAUCAGCCCCAUUCCUGAAUCCACAAAAUGGAAAGGAAAACCGAGAUACUGAGUCUGGAUCAUCUGACUUCAACAGAGUAGCAUGUGCUUACUAUUCUGGGAAAAAUUGGAGUGCUCCAGCUGAGGCUGCAACAAAGGAGGACGAGAGAACAACUAGUGGACCAGGGCAUCAUGCCACCUUUGAAGAGCCCAGCGGCAUUCCAUGAACAGAUAAAAAGCUUGGAACGAGCCAGAACUGAAAACUUUUUGAAACACAAGAUUCGGAGUCGACCAGAUCGUUCUGAACUUGUCAGGAUGCACAUUUUAGAAGAAACAUUUGCAGAGCCAUCCCUGCAGGCUACUCAGAUGAAGUUGAAAAGAGCUCGACUAGCAGAUGAUCUGAAUGAAAAGAUUGCUCAAAGACCUGGUCCUAUGGAGCUGGUAGAGAAAAACAUCCUUCCUGUGGACUCCAGUGUUAAAGAAGCAAUUAUAGGCGUUGGGAAGGAGGACUAUCCCCACACUCAGGGCGAUUUCUCAUUUGAUGAAGACAGCAGUGACGCUUUGUCUCCGGACCAGCCUGCGAGUCAGGAGUCACAGGGGUCAGCCGCGUCCCCAAGUGAGCCAAAAGUUAGUGAAUCGCCAUCUCCUGUGACUACAAACACUCCAGCGCAGUUUGCUUCAGUGUCCCCAACAGUUCCUGAAUUCUUGAAAACUCCUCCAACUGCAGAUCAGCCUCCCCCACGGCCUGCAGCUCCUGUCCUCCCCACAAACACUGUGUCCUCAGCAAAGCCUGGCCCAGCACUGGUGAAGCAAAGCCAUCCCAAGAAUCCAAAUGACAAACACCGUAGCAAAAAGUGCAAAGAUCCCAAACCACGGGUAAAGAAGUUAAAGUACCACCAAUACAUUCCACCAGAUCAGAAGGGUGAGAAGAAUGAGCCGCAGAUGGACUCUAACUACGCCCGCCUGCUCCAGCAGCAGCAGCUGUUCCUGCAACUGCAGAUCCUGAGUCAGCAGAAGCAGCACUACAACUACCAGACCAUCCUGCCUGCACCAUUCAAGCCACUCAAUGACAAAAAUAGUAACAGUGGGAAUUCAGCUUUGAACAAUGCCACACCUAACACACCAAGACAGAAUACAUCUACUCCUGUGAGAAAGCCAGGACCUCUGCCUUCUAGCCUGGAUGACUUAAAGGUAUCAGAACUGAAGACAGAACUGAAGUUAAGGGGUCUGCCAGUGUCAGGCACCAAACCGGACCUCAUUGAGCGCCUAAAACCCUACCAGGAAGUGAACAGCAGCGGCCUUGCUGCUGGGGGCAUCGUGGCAGUGUCAUCAUCAGCCAUUGUCACCAGUAACCCAGAAGUCACUGUGGCCUUGCCGGUUACAACACUACACAACACUGUGACUAGCUCAGUCUCUACUCUCAAGGCAGAAUUGCCACCUACAGGAACCAGCAACGCAACCCGUGUGGAAAAUGUUCAUUCCCCUCUGCCCAUUUCACCAUCUCCCUCCGAACAGUCCAGUCUCAGUACUGAUGACACAAACAUGGCAGACACUUUCACCGAGAUUAUGACCAUGAUGUCGCCUUCACAGUUCUUGAGUUCAUCUCCUUUGAGAAUGACAAAUAAUGAAGACAGUCUGAGUCCCACCAGCAGCACUCUGUCAAACCUGGAACUGGAUGCAGCCGAAAAGGAUCGCAAGCUUCAGGAGAAAGAGAAGCAAAUCGAAGAGCUGAAGAGGAAACUGGAACAAGAGCAGAAGCUCGUGGAAGUGCUGAAAAUGCAACUUGAGGUUGAAAAACGAGGGCAGCAGCAGCGGCCCCUGGAAGCCCAGCCCAGUGCCCCAGGUCAUUCUGUCAAGUCAGAUCAGAAGCACGGCAGCCUUGGCUCCUCCAUCAAAGAUGAGGCCUCACUCCCUGACUGCUCCAGCUCCAGGCAGCCCAUCCCAGUAGCCAGCCACGCUGUAGGCCAGCCCGUCUCUACAGGUGGCCAGACCCUUGUUGCCAAAAAGGCUGUAGUUAUCAAGCAAGAGGUCCCUGUGGGCCAGGCAGAGCAGCAGAGUGUCGUCUCGCAGUUUUAUGUGAGUUCCCAGGGACAGCCACCGCCUGCUGUUGUUGCUCAGCCCCAGGCUUUACUGACCACGCAGACUGCUCAGCUGCUGCUCCCAGUGUCCAUCCAGGGCUCGAGUGUCACCUCAGUGCAACUCCCUGUAGGCAGCCUCAAACUCCAGACUUCACCACAAGCAGGAAUGCAGACUCAGCCUCAGAUAGCAACUGCUGCACAAAUACCAACUGCUGCCUUGGCCUCAGGCUUGGCCCCAACUGUACCUCAGACACAAGACACGUUCCCGCAGCAUGUGCUCAGUCAGCCUCAACAAGUCAGAAAGGUUUUCACAAACUCAGCAUCAUCAAAUACAGUUCUUCCAUAUCAGAGACAUCCUGCCCCAGCUGUCCAGCAGCCCUUUAUCAAUAAGGCCUCCAACAGUGUUCUUCAAUCCAGAAAUGCUCCGCUUCCAUCCCUGCAAAAUGGACCUAACACACCCAACAAGCCUAGUUCACCCCCGCCACCCCAGCAAUUUGUCGUCCAGCACUCUCUAUUUGGGAGUCCAGUCGCCAAGACAAAAGAUCCCCCCCGCUAUGAGGAGGCCAUCAAGCAGACACGCAGCACACAGGCCCCUCUGCCAGAGAUUUCCAACGCUCACAGUCAGCAGAUGGAUGACCUCUUUGAUAUCCUCAUUAAGAGUGGAGAGAUCUCCCUCCCCAUAAAAGAAGAACCUUCUCCUAUUUCCAAAAUGAGACCAGUGACAGCCAGCAUCACCACAAUGCCAGUGAAUACAGUGGUGUCCCGGCCACCACCCCAAGUCCAAAUGGCACCACCUGUAUCUUUAGAACCUAUGGGCAGUUUAUCUGCCAGCUUAGAGAACCAACUAGAAGCUUUCUUGGAUGGAACUUUACCCUCAGCCAAUGAAAUUCCUCCACUACAAAGCAGCAGUGAAGACAGAGAGCCCUUCUCUCUGAUCGAGGACCUCCAGAAUGAUCUGCUGAGUCACUCAGGUAUGCUGGACCAUUCACACUCACCCAUGGAGACUUCCGAGACCCAGUUUGCUGCAGGUACUCCCUGUCUGUCUCUCGACCUGUCAGACUCAAACUUGGACAACAUGGAGUGGUUGGACAUUACCAUGCCCAACUCCUCUUCAGGACUCACUCCUCUCAGCACCACCGCGCCGAGCAUGUUCUCUGCUGACUUUCUAGACCCACAGGACCUACCGCUGCCAUGGGACUAACGUCACAGAUUUCUUUUCUGAGAGUUGAUGAGGUUUAAGAACAUGAAGAUUCUAAAAGGUCAGUUUUUAGAGAUAGAUCUAUAGUUGCAUUGUUGCAAUCAAAAUAUGUUGUCACAGAAAGAAUAGGUGGAAGGUCAUAGCCUGGAACCCAAGUUUGAAAACAUUUCAUUGUGUUCAGUAGUGAAUUUCUACAGUUUAACAUAGCACAGGGCCUUCUGAAAAUCGCACUUGUCAAAGACGACUCAUCUAUUUCUCCAGACUUCAGUAAAGAAUGAAAAGUACCUUUAGAUAAAAACAAAGAAGAGUAAUAUAUGCAGCACAGUGACGUUAGGAUUCUGGUAAUUAACUACAUUUAAAUCUCUGGUCACUUUAAGACCCUAAAUAAAAGGCAGACAGCUCCACUCAAAAACUAAGGCUGAUGUGAGGGAGGUGAGAGGUCACUGCACUUGGUACUUCCUAGAGACGGCCGGAGCCAGGCCCAAGACACAGCAGAGGUCAAAGGCAGUGGAGAGCCUUGGCCAGUUCAGUGACAGCUUCUGGCUGAAGACUUUUGGUUCUAUUCAGAAACCUGUGUCGUUUUUUUGGUGUUGUAGUUUAUUUUGUGAUUUUUUGGAAUCGUACUUUAUAUUUCCAAAUUUAAAUUUAAAUGCAAGAUCUUUCAACAUAAACAGAAGAUACCUACAAAAUACUGUCAGAAGUCCAGGUAUACUGAUAACACUGAAAAUUCUAUUAGCAACCUUCUGGGUUGGUUAGAUUGAUUUUAAUGUAUAUAUUAGACAUUUGUAUGUAUGCUCUGACAUUGUGAUUUGUACAGCCUACGCUGGGGUAAGGAAAUGGGUAUCCAAGGUCCUACUUUUUUAAUAGCUCGAAUAUUUCUAGAGUACUUGAGCCACAUGUAUUUCUGUAUUUAAAGAAUUGCUGACUAACUUUCAGGUAACCAGACCCAUCUCAAAGAACCAAGAAAAGGCUUUAGCAUGAAAUAUCUUUCUGAGCUGGCGAGUUAGAAGAAUGGAAGGUAAGGGGAAGGUCUGUCAUCUACCCAGGACAUUCCCAUGAUGAGUACAGGUCAGAUUGUGCCACAAGGUGGGCCUCCACGUCCCUGCCCUGGCCCUCUUUCUUCUGUCACUAACCCUGGUUAUCAUUUUACAGGCUUGUAACUGGAUAUUCUACCAGAGCUCUCACUAUAUUGUCAAGCCUAAGAUUGAAAAACUGGAGGCUUUAUUAGUGUUUUUAUAUAGAAAACAGUUAUUACAUAUGUGUUAAGUCAUUUCUUAAGAAUUUUCUAAAAUGCCAACUAUCACAGGAUUAUUUCAAGCUAGUCAUUGAGGUAUAUGACAAAAUGUAAAUAACAAAAAACUGAAAUCUACCAAAAGAGCAUGGAGAUUUUUCUUAAAUAAUAAUAUUGUGCUCUCCACCUCACCCUUGUGUAAACCCUCAGGUCAGGUUGGUUCCCCUGGGUCACAAAAUGGUAAAUGUUCCAUACUGACAUGCCGGAGGCAGCCUGACCCGUUAUUUGGAAAGAAUUUGUGAAUUAUUUCUGGGUUUGUGUUUUGCCUAAGAGCUGAUCUUAUUUCUGAUUUGUGUGUGUGUGGUUUAUAAAUUUUACUACGUGUAACAAAAGUCUGCUUUUCCAGCAUGAGCACACUGGAGCCCUCUGCUCACUGGCACUUCCUGACUCAAAGGCACUAACAGUGCUCAUGUGCCUUCCAGACGGUUCAAGGCAGAGGCCACUGUGCUCAGUGUAGUCUGUGAUGAAUAGUUUAAGUGUUCAGAAAUUGGUAAACCAACACACGGGAUACAAUAACUCUCUGUUAACCAGAACACCGUCAUUUGACCAAGCCCUACAAGAGUUUACCACACUAGAUGUUCUGUGAAUCCUCGAGUCAGUUCCAUUGAGAGGGGCCUGUCUCCAGGGCCAGGCUAUUUACUUGGGAAAGUAUUUUUCUUACAGUUCUUGGCCACAGUUUUUUUGCUGAGGGUUUCUGUCUGGGCCUAUCAGGUCCAUACUUAGACCCUGAGCAUCUUCUUCAUUCAGAUUUGAAUGGCUUAUUAAAUUAGCACCAAAUAUCAGUGGGACUGUAGAAGGUAACCGAACACUAGUACCAUUGACUCUCGUUGAAUAACUUUAUAUUUCCAUAAUCCUGAAUUGUGUAGAUAGUUUUCUAGCUCUCGGGUCCCUUUAUUGCUUUUUAAAAUAGGGUUUGAAACAUGCCACAGGAAGGUUGCUCUCCAAAAAUACACAGUGCAGUGCAAGAAAAUGCUAUCUCAUUGGCCUACUCUCCUAUGAAUUGCUAAAGUGCCCACUUCACAUAUGUGUUUAAACCUUUAUAAACCAGUAUUUCACUUUUAAAAAGACAAGGCAUCUCUACCCAUUAACUCUGCAAGCCACUCCACUUGCACCAUUCCGCUUGACCCUCCUCUCUCCUGGCUUGGGUCACCAGCCAGGCACCUGUGACACGAGUGCUGCUCUCCAGGAUCUCCACUACAUGUUCCAGGUUGGAGUGAGGACGCGCUAUGUGCUCACACUCAUGUGACAUGACCAAAGAUGAUACUCUGUAAACAAGGCCCUUCUGACCGGACUCAGUGCGUGUGAUGGUGAGUGCAAUGAGGAAGGGUGGAUAUUGACUAAAGACUGGUUGUUGUUGUUGUUUAGGUUAGUGUCACAGCCAUUACAGCACAAGUCAAAGUCGCCAGUUGAAUUUUCAUUAUGCACGUGUGUGGUUUAAGCAGUGGUACUGUUGUAUAUCAUAUUGUAAAGUAUCAUACUGCCAAGAAAAUAACUCCUAGAAAGGCAUUAUCUCACAUCCCCAUCUUACUUUCCUACAUGUUCUCAAAACACAGUAGUACCAGCCUUACCUUUCUGCUGUAUGUAGAUAGUCAGAUCAUCCUACUGGGGGUGGGAUGAAUUUAAAAGUUAUACCAAAAUUUCUGUAAAGUCUUUGAAAGUCUAGGAGUAGGUGGUCAUCUUGUACAUUUCAGCAAAGCAUCCACUAGGAAACCUCAUAGGACAGUGUUAGUGGUUCACGUUCUAGUGUUUUUCCUGAAAUGUGCAAUCUACUGUAUAGUAUUGCCACAUAAUUGUACAUAGAUGUAUUCUGAAUUUGUGGAAUUUCUUGCUUAGAUACUAUUGUGUUUGUUUCAUAUGAAUAUUUUUGUAAUUCUAAAAGAGAUCUUAUUUAAAUUUCCUUUUUAAAAGCCGCAUGGUUCUGUGAUCCAUGUAACUGACACUUUUUGGCUUUCAGUGCUGUUUAGAAACAGUGGCAAAGGCAGGGUGGUGCUGCCUGCAAGCUGCUGCCUAUGGAAGGCAAAGUCAUAGUAAUGAGAUAGCACCUCUGAACUGUGCAGUCAGCAUACCCUGAGUGAUGGCUCAGGGGCGCACUACCUAUUUUGUCACCAGAGCUGACUCAGGCUUCCUGGACCCUCAACCCCAGAUCAUUCCAGGCAGCAUAGCUUUCUUCACAGUCCUUUCAGAAUUCCCAGGCUGAAAUCAGCCAUAGCAGUUGACAAAACAGCUAUCCCCACAAGUGAUGAGAUAGUCCCUUUACUGUCCUCAAAUGGACUUGGCCUUAGAGACGUGGUAAAGCACUUUGGCAGGGUUUAAAAUAUUUGUGAGAAGCCCACAUUUCAGUAUACAUCCUCACUGGCUUCCAUGCACCCACCUGACGGUAGCCUCACAGAAGUCCUGGCUGUCACUCAGGUGGGGAGCUCAUGGUGCCGCUGGGGACUUUUUAGAGAAAUGUAAAGAGAAUAGCUAUUCAGUGUCUACUAGCAGAGCAACAUGUGUCAAUUUAACCAAAUUCACAAAUAACCCUCCAUUUUUCAAUAUCUGCUACUGUAAACAUGAAUAUUGAAUACUGACAAGAGAAUACCCAUACAAAUCGUCCCACCGCCCUAGAGGCCACAGAAUUAGCCCAAAAUUAUCAAAGAACAUUAACUGGAAGGUCAGGUUUUUCAAGGAACAUAGCUUACAAAUGCAUCAGUGUGUAUCUGGAGAGCAUCCUAACUGCAUUUCAACUCAUCUUUUAAGUGAUUUCAGUCAAAACUGGAAAACAACUAAGAUGUAGUAAUUUUUUUUUCCUGGUUCAAACCUUCAAUAACUUGCUCAUUCAGCAGUCUCUCUGAGCUACAUUUUUAUUUGUAAAGUGACUCUGUCUGCAUGGCAAUGAGCAGGUGCGUGUUUUUUCCACAUUCGCCCUUUCUUGCAGUAUCCAGGGAAACACAUCAUUACAAAGGGUUUCUACCUGAAAUCUUUCAUGGAAGGCCUACAAUUCGAAAAGCUGCACAUGUUUACAGAAGAGCUCUUACCCUCCAUGCAAACACUUUGCUCUGUGGUGUCACAGCUUUGUGACAAUAAGAUGGCAAUCUCGGAUCUACAAGGUGCUGUCGGGAAUCAAAUAAAAUAUGUUAUCAGAGAUAUCAUCACAUCUAUAGUGUUUAACAGAGCUUUAUGCCAACUACUAAGACAAAGCUUUAACAAAGUUUAUAGAAUACUGAAACUCGUAACAAUUACCUCUCUACGUGAUGCUGUAAGGAAUCUUGCUAAUUUGGUAGGAAGAGGAAGCAUUUAGGAAAGGGUUUAGUAUCUACCAAAAGUACUUGACCUCAAGUAACCAAUAGUAAUGCAAACUUGCUUUAAAGGAACCAAAGGCAUUGCCAAGUAUUUGCCAAAAGGAGGCACUUUUUAUUUAAAAUUUGAGACUAAUGAGAUCUCAAAAAUCAGCCCCAAAAAGGUAUUAUCCAUUUAAGGUUAUAAUUUUCACUAAGAUGUAGAUAUUUCUCUUAUUGUUUUCAUGUAAAAUAGUAUAGAGUUGUUUUGUUGGUUUAAGAGUAACAUUCAGUAGUAAUACAAAGUUUUUUUUCUAUGUAGAAAUUAGUUUUCUUUUCUUGCUUGCAAUAGAAAUGCAAUGUGAUAGGUGUUUCUCUUCUUAUUUUCAUUGUCACAUUAUGUCUUAGCAUCUCACUUUAUGAAAAAAAGGAGAAAGAUACCAAUCUACAGAGCCCUGCUUGUUGAAGCACUAGUUUAAUCAACAAAAAAUUAUGGCAAUCGGGGGUCCAUUCAUCUAUUGCCUUUAUGUUGUUUUUUAAAAGAAAAACCAUGAUGCCUUUGUAUUUGCUGUUUGCACCCCUGAAAUCAAUUCCAUAUCAUGUUUGAAUGCCAUACAUUUUGCACAUGUACUGUACAUAAGUAAUGCAUACUGUAUUUUUAUAUGUGUGCACAUUUAUCAUCAGAUCUUUUGUACAUAGUGGCAGUAUUGUAGCUGAUCGGGAAAUGUUUGAUAUCUCAGCAAUUUUGCAUUUUUGUGUCUCAAAUAAAAGACAUUUUGAUGUACUAUGA